GUGUGUGGACGGAAUUCGGGACCGACUGACGGCCGGCCGGCUUCCCGGAACUGGAAGGUUACAUUGAUUACCCACCUAGUACAACAUCUUACGGGAAGAGCAUAGUAUUUCCUAGAGGAAUAUGAACAUAACAGGAAGGUAUCAUUGGCUCUGAAUUAAAUUUGAACUUGUCCCCUGAAUAGCUACAGGUUUUGGAAGCUGAAUCAAUGUUAUCAGAUGAGUUAGAAUCCAAACCAGAGCUCCUGGUACAGUUUGUUCAGAAUACGUCCAUCCCAUUGGGACAGGGGCUUGUAGAAUCAGAAGCUAAAGAUAUUACUUGCUUGUCCCUCCUUCCCGUGACUGAAGCCUCAGAAUGCAGUCGGCUAAUGUUACCAGAACCUGUUCCAUGGAGAGAAGAGGAUGGAAAGUCAGGCUGCAGUGACUUGAAUGAUACUACAAAUCAUUCUAACUCCUCCAAGGAGGUCCCUUCCUCAGCUGUUUUGAGAAGCCUUCGGGUGAAUGUGGGUCCAGACGGAGAGGAGACGAGAGCUCAGACUGUACAGAAAUCCCCGGAGUUUUUGUCCACUUCAGAGUCUUCUAGCUUGUUGCAAGAUCUACAGCCAAGUGAUAGCACUUCUUUUAUUCUUCUUAACCUAACAAGAGCAGGUCUGGGCUCUUCAGCUGAGCACUUAGUGUUUGUACAGGAUGAGGCAGAAGAUUCAGGGAAUGAUUUCCUCUCCAGUGAGAGCACAGACAGUAGCAUUCCAUGGUUCCUCCGGGUUCAGGAGUUGGCCCAUGACAGUUUGAUUGCUGCUACUCGUGCACAACUGGCAAAGAAUGCAAAAACCAGCAGCAAUGGAGAAAAUGUCCACCUUGGUUCUGGUGAUGGGCAGUCAAAAGAUUCUGGGCCCCUUCCUCAAGUGGAAAAGAAGCUCAAGUGUACAGUUGAAGGUUGUGACCGGACAUUUGUAUGGCCAGCUCACUUUAAAUACCACCUCAAGACUCAUCGAAAUGACCGCUCCUUCAUCUGUCCUGCAGAAGGUUGUGGGAAAAGCUUCUAUGUGCUGCAGAGGCUGAAGGUGCACAUGAGGACCCACAAUGGAGAGAAGCCCUUUAUGUGCCAUGAGUCUGGCUGUGGUAAGCAGUUUACUACAGCUGGAAACCUGAAGAACCACCGGCGCAUCCACACAGGAGAGAAACCUUUCCUUUGUGAAGCCCAAGGAUGUGGCCGUUCCUUUGCUGAGUAUUCUAGCCUCCGAAAACAUCUGGUGGUUCACUCAGGAGAGAAGCCUCAUCAGUGCCAAGUCUGUGGGAAGACCUUCUCUCAGAGUGGAAGCAGGAAUGUGCAUAUGAGAAAGCAUCACCUGCAGCUGGGAGCAGCUGGGAGUCAAGAGCAGGAGCAAACUGCUGAGCCACUAAUGGGCAGUAGUUUGCUUGAAGAGGCUUCAGUACCCAGUAAAAACCUGGUGUCUAUGAAUUCCCAGCCCAGCCUUGGUGGAGAGUCCUUGAACCUACCAAAUACCAAUUCUAUCCUGGGAGUUGAUGAUGAGGUGCUUGCUGAAGGAUCCCCACGUUCCCUGUCUUCAGUGCCUGAUGUGACACAUCACCUGGUGACCAUGCAGUCAGGGAGGCAAUCAUAUGAAGUUUCUGUCUUAACUGCAGUAAAUCCACAAGAGAGUCUCGCUCCGUUGCCCAGGCUGGAGUGCAGUGGUGCGUUCUCGGCUCACUGCAACCUCUGCCUCCCAGGUUCAAGCGAUUCUCCUGCCUCAGCCUCCUGAGUAGCUGCUACUACAGUUACUAAACCAAGGAGAUUUAACUGAAAGACGGACAUGAGCGUGGGUGCUGACUCCUGGAAGAGCAACUCUAUCUGAUCUCAAAAUGCGUAUACUGGGAACAGGAUGCCUUAGCCCACAACAGAACCAGAAUGAAUCUUUGAAGGCACAAGACUCUGCUUUUGCCACUCUUCCUCUUUCCUGGUAUAGAAGAUGGAUGUAGGAGAGCUUCUUUUCUAACUACCAUCUGAUCAGACAAGGAAUGAAGCAAUGACUGUGGGCUGGGAAACUGUACCUACCUCUCUUCCCACUGCAAAUUUCUGGGAUAGACCAAAAGUGAAUUUGAUUAUGUGUUGGCUGAAGUUCUUCAUUCUGACUGUUGAGGGGAGGUUUUCCUUUGAAGAGUUUUCAUCCCAGACUCAGCUGUCUUUUCACAUGGAUGAAAUAAUUCCUGCUACCAACAACAGAGCUUCACCAGGAAGUUGAGUUUUCAAGAUGCCUUGUUGCUUUGAAGAAGGGAGUGAUGUCAAUUCUCUUGUUACAUUCUCCCUUUAGCAACCUGAGUAAGAGACUCUCUGCCACUGGGCUGCAAAAAAAUAAAUUACUUGAAUCUCCCCUUGGCCCAGGCUGAGGUACUAUCUUGUCCUAUACACUUCUACUUGGUCACUUUGCUUUCUUCGUUAAUGGAACAUACAGUAGCAUGUUAAGAGGGAUUUCAUGUUUUUGUUUUUUUAAAGUUAAAAAUUACAUGAUGCAGAGAUUCAGGUUUUCCUUUAAAUAAACAAAACAGCCCAGUCAGUUCUUUGGCUCUUGUUUUAUACAAAAUUUGUUUUCUUAGAGAUUAAGAAUUUAAUCUUUCCCUUUAAAAUAGUGUAUUGAUUUACCCUUAGGAUUCCAUACCAGUAAAACUGAACCGAGGAGUCUUAGGAAACAACAAGAACAUCUUCAUUUCUUAAGCCCAGGUGAUAGUUACUCUGUCACCACCAAAAAAGACGCAUCUGAGAAAAUGGCAAUAAAAACAGAUACUUCUGAAUUUUUCCA